AGUAGAAAUACUUUUAUUAAAAGUCUUAUCUUUACAUAAAUUUGCCAAAUUAUUAAUUUUGCUUGAAAGGGAAAGGUGUCCAACUUCAGUUGGAAAUACUAGUUUCUAAGAGAUACUGCUGAGACUAAGAGCAUAAAACAUGAUGAAAACCUUAAGUGGCUAAGUGCAGCAACGUCAGAGUAAAAGCUUUGAUGAAGUCUUGGUUUGCUUGGGCUGUGUAGGUUGGAGGCUCAGCCUUUGUUUCUCCCUCCUCUGGUGCCCAGUGGUGGUGUUUGUGUCCGUGAAUUUUCAACCUCUGUAGUUUGUUUGUAGUUAUGACCACUGUUGCACCGAACCCUUACCGAGGGCCAGGCCCUGUGCUAAGCACUUGCCAGUGUGGAUUUAUUAAGUCUUCAUGACAGCACCAUGUAGGGGGAGCUGCGUCCCUGUGUUGUACUUGGGACGCGAUCUGACCUCAGGCACUUCAGGCUCCUGAAGGGUCUGCAGUCUCGUCUCUGCCUGGGAAACCACGAUUUGCAGCAUAUUCCACAGACCUCAUGCUCAUCAUCAGGAGGCUUCCCGGGACUGCUGCCUGAGAUUUCUAAGUUCCUAAUGUGGUUCAUGCUUCUGGUGAGUUUCUUUGAGGCGACGCCCCCUGCGUUGCCUCUGGUCAGCUCAGUCCUGUGGUCCUGCAGGGCAUCCUACAGUGUCCUCUGUCUGUGACUUGUGCCGUGCCACCUUGACCUGGCAUCCACUGUCCUCUACCGCGUUUGCAGAUAGGAGCCACUGUUGGUGCCUUUUUGUCGUGUGUGUUGAAUGGUCAGGGUCCCAAAUAGCUGAUUGGGAGCACUCUCCUUGAAUCUGCCAUGUGCCUGGGUCUCAGGUGACUGGGCCCCUCCUUGCUUCAGAACCCACGUGCGUUGCCUGUCCUCUCUGGCUUGGAGGGUUGUGUGGAAUCAGAGGUGAGACCCAGUCCCCAGGGAUGGGCAGUUGCCUUUGAUUGCCCAGCUGUCCUCAGCGCCCUCCCUCCUGCGCCCAACUGCUGUCUCAGUUGCUUGCUUGAGGAUCCGGAUAUAGACUGAGGUCGGCCUUAGCGUGGCGGGGGGUUUUCUCUUGAGUCUUGGAUACUUUGUUACCGGUCCCAUCUUCCUGUGGGUGGGAGUGUCUGUCUUGCUUGGCCCAGCCUCCCAGAGACCUUAGCUCUCUUAGUACAUGGGCUCUGCCUACCUUGAUCCCCAGCUCACCACCCUAGUGCAGUUGCUUCUUCGCUCUUGUUCCACUCCUUGUCGCCAUCCACCCUGUGCUUUCUCGAUGUGUCCUUACUCGGUGUUUCUGUGGAGCAGGGCAUCCUGGGCUUCCUUUCUGAUCCCUGGCUCCUGUGAUCUUCCGUGCUGGGCUCCCUCUUCCCUUCCCUUUUCCACUGUGUUGCCCUCACACAGCUGGCAUGCCAUGGAUGUCGCUCACCCAAGCCCUUCCUAAUGUUGCUCACCAAAACCCCUCCCACCUUGCCCCUGGGACCUUCUCCCCUUCCAGGCUGCAUGCAGGCCGAGGGCCUGGCGUCUCAGCAGGAGGCAGUGGGGCCUUUGCUGGCACCUGGGCUCUGCAUCCUGACCUUCUGAGGGCUUGGUCCUUUAGGUCCAUCUUGAAUCUCCUCCAGGCUUCGGACUCUCUGCUCUGUAGCUGGCCCAUGGAGACGGGUACACUCAGGCCUGGUCUUAGACUCCGCUGCUUGGGCUGUGCUGGUGCCUUUGGUGCCCUCUUAGUCCAUCCCACCUGGGGGCCCUGUCCUGCUGUCCAUUGUGCCAGAGUGCUGUCCCCUUGUCUUUCCGUAACUGGCUGCUCGUUACCUUUCCCAUCUCAGCCUCAGUACCAGCCACUUGGUAUCAGGGAGGCUCUCCCUGACCAACCUAAAGUUCACAGCCGUGGUUGCCAGUUUAAAUUUCUGCAUAGCAACUUUUUGGUUUAUUUUGGCUACUUAUCUUCCCCAUCAUGCCCCCUGUCCCUCCCAUAUAAACUCAGUGAGAGUAGGGGCCACAUCUCAUCAUCCUGCCCACAGCUCUGCUGUCUGUAUCAGCCAGGGUAUGCUGUGCAGAGGCUCACGGUAAAUAGCUGCAGACCACGAAUCCCAUCUGCUUGCUGUGCUUUAAUAUUGGCUUACAUCUUUGGAUCCAGUGAGUUCUUUUCUCUGUCUCCCUCUCUCUCACUCGCUCAUACUUACUUUGUGUAAUUGGUGAUUUCCAGCCUUUUGUAUAGUCCUUUCUCGAAUAGUUGUUUUCUGUCAUCUUGGCGGGGGCCUCAAGGGGUUGACUGUACGGAGGGCAGGGGCUGCAGAGCUGCAGCUGCUGCCUGGGGUCUCACGGCGCCCGUGAGGUGUAGGCAGGUGCUUUGCCUCUGAGCUGUCUGUAGAAUGGGGUGACGGCGGUUUCAUCAGACUCAGUGAAGCAUGUCAUACAGUGAGUGUCUGGUCACAGCAGGAAGAUGGUGAAUGUCAGCUAAUGAGUAUUCAUCACCAAUGAAUAGUAACAGUUUUUUUUACUAAGGCUAUGUAAUGUAGCCUCAGAAUUCCACUCAGCACAGCCCCCUGGCAGCGGUGCCUCUGAGAGCUGGCAUGAUGGAGAGAGCCUGGUUGGCCUUACUGGUGUGGUUGGGGCACUUGGGAGAACGCCUUCCUCACAAAGCUCAUCUGGAGGGUUUUCGGACUUGUAGGAUAGCUUUUUCAGGGGCCUUGCCUUUGGCAGGGCAGGGACGUGUACUGCUGCAGUCUAGGGUAUGGGAUAACUUUCUAAACCAGACCCAGAACUUCAUGGCCGCAGGGGCCUUUUAGCCAUGCGGGGCUAGGAGCUGACACAGCGUCAGCAGCAUGAGGGCCUGUGGUGCUGGGCGGCAGAGCCCAGAGGGAGCCCCUGCUGGUGUGACUUUAGUGUAAAGGCUGGGGGAUACCAGAUUCUUACAGAAGACUUAAGACGGGCACAGUGAUGUCUGCUCUUUGACCCUUGCAGUAUGAAUUAGUAAAACUGAAAUUAUUACAUUUCCUUUAUUAGGAUUAUAAAAGCAAUGAUGACUUAUUGAAGAAAAUUUGGAAAAUACAGAAACUACCUAUAAUUUUUCCAUUGUUAACAUUUGAGCAUAUUUCUUGUCACUUUUAAUGGUGCUUUAAAUAUGUAGCAAAUGUAUCAUUUCGUAUUUUAAAAAAAUGCUAGGUAAGCAUUUCCUCCUGUCCUUAAAAAGCUCUUUUAAACAACUUUAAAAUAUUGUAUAGAUAGAUGUACACAAUUUUCUGAAUAAUUGGAGUUAUAUUUACAUCUUUUCACUCUUUAGGAAAGGACUGGCCUGUUUCUGUGUUGGGUUCCUUCCUGAGUGUGGCUUCCAGCUCAGUGGCUCAGACUUCAAGAUGAAGACUUCAGUCCUGGUUGUGUAUGGUCUUGGGCCAGUUACCAUAUGUCUAAUGAAUACUUAGUUUUGUCAUCUACAAAAUGAAAAUAGUAAUAUUUGCCUCAAAGACUAUUAUUUGGGAGGAUCUAGUGCAAAUGUUAGUAAUGUGGAUAUUGUGUAGUGUCCCAGGAUAUUAAUGUUUUUAGCCUCUUGGCUUUUAUUCUGUAUUGUUGCCCCAAAAGAUGAUGCUCACUUAUCUUUCAUCCAGUGUAAGGAUAUCUGGAAAGACAACAGAAAGUAUAGCUGUUUUCAUUUCAAAAGUGAUCAGCUGCUUGAGCUAGCAAGCAAGGCUUGCACUAGCUUCCAGGCGCAGUCACGCAGUUUCACAGCAGGCGCGGUUCCCUCGGAGCACCCAGAGCUGCCCUGCGGUAGUCAGCAGUUGUGCUGUGGCUGCACUGCCAGGCUGGGUGGCAGGUGGAUCGGAGCCAGCAGAUGUGGCUCAGGAAGUGCCUUCUUGGCCUCUCCUUAAUCUCUUUCAGAGUCUGUGGGCCCUUGAUUGCACUGUGGGUUGUUUCAGACUCCAGUAUUAGGAGACUGAACCCCUUGGUGGUUUUUUUGUGUGUGUGUGCUGAGCUGGGUUGAGGACAUGUUAAGCAGGUGGGGUGCCUCCCCUGGGUUUGCUCCGGGUGGUACCUGUGGUGUGGGGUGGUUCUGAGUAGUUCUGGCCCCACUGCUGGAGUAUCUGCCCACUCAGUUUGUGAGAUGGCAGGGCUUCAUCCUGGUCUGGUGCCUCAUUUUCUUCUUUAGCAGUGGGCUUAGAACCAAUGCAGAUUCCCAAGUUAAGUAUUUUUUCUGUAGCUUAAUUAUUACAGGCUUCUGGUACCUAAGCCCUUUCUUACUUUCUGUUCUGAGGGGAAGAGAAGAUAAUGUUGUUUCUCCGCCCCCCCCCGGAGUGGCCCCAGGACCUUGCAUGGCAUUUGCAGCAUUUGCAGCGUGCUUGGGUUUGCUUUACUAGGGUGAAAGUGUUGCACCCCCCAGCACCCACAAAGGCACCUCUGCUCACACUCCGGUGAGGUUCUGACUGGCCCUGGGACAUCACCUGCUCCAGGAUCCUAUGUGGCUCAUCCCAGGAGAGAUGUGGGAGGGAAGGGGAAAAAAGGCUUACAUUUGCUGAGUGGAAUUCAUGUAGAUCUGAGUUCCGCAUUGAUUCCUAAGCUGCAGAGCCCUUAUGCCUUGGCUGUUUUGUGAAUGUUAGUCGGUCUUAACCUUUUUCACCGAGUUAGCAUUGGCUGUCUCAGGAGGCUCACAGCUCCUGCUCCUCCUCCAGGGGAGUGCGCCCUCCUCCUCUGUCGGUAGCUGUCAGGUGCCCCUUUCCUCUGCAGCAGACUGUCCUGGGUCCUUGCCUGGCCUUCCCCUUACACGUGAGCCUGCAGCUUCAUUCACAGCCCCUGUGUAGAAAGAUAGGCACAUCGAUAGGUCCCUCCCUGCCCAGAGUGGGCGGAACUGAGGCAGGCACUAAAAGCAGCUGACUGGCAGCCCUAGAAACAUGAAGGGUUUCAUUUAUAGUUUCAGUCCUUUUCCUUCUUUCGAGCCUUAAUUUAAAAAAAAAAAAAAAAAAAGCCUUGAAGUCCUGCUUCUGAGUUUUCUAAUUUGUGCAGGUAUUAGUUGCCUUGUAACAUAAUCAAAAAUAAAUAAAAAUGAUUUAUAAUUAGCUUAUUAACUGUAUCAGUAAAUGGAUACUUUAAAGAGGAUCAUUGAUCCCUCAAAAUAGAAGCAAUGCAGUCAUUCCCUCAUUAUGCUUUACUUGUGAUUUGCUUACAACCCACUCUUCCUAGUUAAAGUUAAAUAUUAAUCCAGACCCUAUCAGUGCGAUGUAGUAGUGUCUGAAUCAGUUGUUGUUUUGGUGUAAUCGUAUCAAAGCAUGUUAUAAAAUCUACAAAAUUGCAGGGUUAACUCCAAAUAUUUUCACUAAGGUAUUGUUUUUUUGGGCAAAAAUGCAUAGUGAACAUUGUGGAGCUGAAGUGAGGGAACUUCGAUUUCUGAGAAACCACUAGUUUUAAGGGUUUUGAAGGAAGAGUUGGAGGAGGAGAGGAAGAGAAUAAAUUCACAGUUAAUGAGUUUCCAGUAUUUUCUGUCGCAUUUUACGUUGUAAUGGAAAAGACUGGGAACUGAACUCACAUGCAGUUUGUCAAAUCACUUUUUCCCUAGAAUUCAGGAUUGAUGAGAUUAACGGGGUGUUAAAGGUAAACUGAGGCACAUAAUUAACAUGGACAGAACUGUAGACCUGAGUGUUGAGAGUUGGGAAAUUUCAGUGAGUUGGGAAGACUGGAAGCACCUGUUCUUCAGAGUGCAGGUCCUCAUAUUCAGUGGGUUUAAGGUGCUGAAACUUUUUUUUUUUUUUUGAGAUGGGGUCUUGCACUGUUGCCCAGACUAGAGUGCAGUGGUGUAAUCACCACUCACUGUAGCUUCGAAUCCUGGGCUGUCAGCCUAUCCUCCCACAUCAGCCUCCUGACUAGCUGGACUGCAGGCCUGGGCCAAAACUCCUGGCUUGAAACUUCUUGUAACCAGAUUGGAGGAGGAGGGCAUGUUCAUUUUCGUGACGUUUCCUUUCCCUUAAACAUCCAGUGAAAUCUGACCUUUGACCAUCACUUUGCUUAAAAGAAGCUACUGGAUUUAAAGUCUAGGAGAAUGUCCUAGACAAGCCCAUAGUAUGUUCCUGUAUGUUCCCCACCCAGAGACCUGCGUUAUGAAGUGUUUGGUGUGCUUCUUCCAGCCCCACUGUUCUUUCUAAAGUGUUUUAUUUUACAUACGCUGUCCUGGCUUCUGGGCUAUGACCUUUGCCUUUUUUGCCCUUUAGUUCCUUUGCCCUUUACCUACUGCAGUGCAGCUGCCUGUCCUUGGGUUGACUACAAAGAAGUCACCUUUGAACAACUUAGAAAUUGUGACUUUUGGGGAAGGCAGGGCAGAGCCUUGGGGCUGAGAUGGGGGAGGAGCCAGCUCUGCCCUGGGAGAGAUACAAAGCGCCUGCCUGGGUGAGGCAGUGCACGGGUGGGCUUGCUUCACCUCUUUGGCCCCAGCUUCAAAACCAGCCAGUCCUCCCUGGCUUUGGCUUUAAUUCACAUUUACAAGCUUGAAAACCAGUUAAUCCCAUUAGCUCAGCUUCUAAAGCUGAAAAUCGUCCCCUAAAUGGGUCACCUGUUGUCAUCAAUAGCUUUAUUAGCUAUGGAAUAAUAUAGUUUUGUUCUCUAACUGUAGGAUCCUUCUUUUGCUCUUAAAAUAGCUCAGUAAGUUGGGUCUCAUAAAUACAUACAGCAAGCAUAUACCAGAUACUAAAAUACAAAAACAUUGCUGAUCUUGCUUUUCAGUACUAAAAGCAGAAAAUCGGGAAUUUACUAAAUUGAGAAGUCAGUCAUUACCUUUCGAUGGGUUUGGACUCUUGCAAGGCAGUGAUUGUAAACGAGAGUGAUCUUUUGUUGUUUUUCAAUGAACUUUAUUCUCUAAUUUUUAGUAAAGCACACUAGGAAAUAAUGCUUCAGAAUUCUGUUUUCGAGUAGUUUCCUGACUAAAAUAAAAAUUCACUAAAAAAAACCUCUGCUGUCACCAUUUCCUUUUUUCUUAAGAUAACUAGGAAAUGAAUCAUUAAGAGUUUGCUCCGUGGCAAUGGAUCGGGAAGCUGACCCUGCUCUCUGUGGGGCUGGAGCCUUGCUAAUGUCCCAGGAUUUCACUUCACAGAGACAAGCAUCAGAGGCUUGCUUCAUUUAUAGAUCCUACUUCUUUUCUACACCACAGCCAACUCAAAAUGGUGACAGAAUCUAAGACGAGGCUAGAAGUCACCACGGAGCAGUUGGAAGCUCUGCUUCCGGUUCUGGGGGCAGUGUUCCUGGCGUUGUGUCCUUUGGCCCCACCUCAGUUUGUCCGUUUAGCUCCUCAGCUGAGAAUGAGAUGUGUAUCAUAUAGGAGUUUCCUGGGCCACUCACAGCCCCAAGCUGGAGAGUGCCAGCCUAAUGUGUCAGGAGUAGGGGGUGAGGCCAGAGGGCUGUGUGCCAACUCCUCCCUAAGAAGCCUCCUGGGAAAGCCCUCCCAGGCACUUCCCAGGUCUCACUGGCCGCCUGAGGCUGCAGGGGAGGAUGGUCAGGCCGCCUCUUGGCUGGCACUGCUUCCCGGCGUGCCGCCAGCCUUUCUCAUGGGGAGGGGAAUGAUGGCAUGCCUGGGGGGCAGCAGGGCCCCAGGGCUGCCUAGGGCUCUCACUGUGUCCUCCUGGUUCUGAGAUGCCACCUUUGUGAUCCACUGUAGAGGGAUUUAUUCUAUUAUGAUCAAUGCAUAGAAAUUUCUUCGAUUUGGAGACUGAACACUAGUGAGCAGAACUGAAAUUGAGCUUUAAAAGAUAUUGAUGACGGGUCUGUGGAUAGGAGACUUUAGUGUGGUUUUUAUGCAGACGUCCUGCCAGCUGUAAAUUCCCUGGAGGUUUGGUAUGUGAGAACAUAAGACUAAACUUAUUUCUAUUUUGUUGAGGAGAAAUGAUUAAAACUUUUCAUUGAUGUACUUCUGUGGCAGACUUUUUGGAGAAUUGAACCAGCGGGCAUAUUCAGUAUUUGAAGUCAUAGAUGAGUAAAGGAGGUAUGUUGUAGUUUGCGCUGGCGGCGUGGCCUGUGGUCGGCAGGGCUUAUCUGUGAAGGUAUGUGCACAGCUUCCUAAGGCAGUGAAAAGUCCUGGCAGUGUUAGUAUUGAAUGAGAUAAUCCAAAAAAUGUAAAAAUGUUUACAUUUUUAAAGGGAUAGUUGGCGAUUUAAAUGGUUUCUGCUAACAAAUCAAAUUAUUCAUUGCAGAGGUAAAAUAUUUUCAGAAUGUUAAUUUUAGAUGUCGUAGAGAGUGUACAUCAGCAAUGACAAGGUCAGCAAAAUAUCUUAGCAAAACUUGAUUGAUUGAUUCCAUGCACAGGCAAGCGCUGUUCUGGGCACCGGAGACGGAGCAGUGCGCUGUUGCGUCCAUCCACAGAUGGCCUCCAGAGUCAUGCGGUUGCAGGGAGGCCGAAGGGCCAGGGAGGCCGCUGGGUGGGCACGGCUGGGCGGUGCCCUCACGUGGGUUUUGUUGGGCUACUCUUACUGUGCACUUUUUCUCAGUUUGGUCAGUGUUCCGCCUUGCUGCCUGGCCCCCAACCCUCGCCCUCUGAGGGCCUCACAAAGAGCCAAGCAGAAGGCAGGCUGGGGGCUUUUCAGGCCAGCCCAGAGGAUGUAAUGAUGAUGGUUGGCACUGUCCCACGGCCGCCACCAGUCUCACACUGCCUCGUGGGCAGUCCUGGAGUCGUGCGGCACCUUGCUGGUCCCUGCUCUCCUUGAAGAAGGGCCAGUGGGGCACUUCGCCAGAGCCUUCUUGUCUGACUCCGUCAUCCAAGAGGCAUGGAUGGCCGGGCCCCCGGCAGUUUCCAUUCUAUUCUGAGAAGGCAAAACAAAAUUAUUCCUGUCUCUUAUUAUCUAAUAUUUGUUACAGCAGUUGCUCACUUUUAGGUGCAUUUUAUUACAGAUUUCAGACAGGUGUGGUUAUUAGUGCAGCUUACUGUUUGGACACAAUGCCAAGGUCAGGAGGACAGUGUUCCCCUGAGCACCACUUCUGCUAGGAGCAUGGGCAGGCCAUGCCUCGCCAUUAAUCUCUCCUGAUUUAGGGGAGGAAUACCAGGCCACCCCCUCUUCUCCCUGUGCAAGGGAACAGACAUUUGACAAAAACGGAUGCCAUGUUACGCUGAUUUUGUGUGUCUAAGGCAGACUGCAGCAGGUGUUAUCUCCGUGCUCUUCCUUUCCUGGAGUGUUGAGCAUCUCUUGAUAGUAGGGGAUGCCCCUGAGGGUGGUGAAUGUGGCUGCACAGGUCCUGAAAGCUAUUUGAUGUUGCCGUUACUUCAGGUAGAACUUAAAGUUGACAGUACAUUCUACUCUGCAGGUGGAAAUGUGGAGUGCCAUUUUGACAAAUUGGAAUGCCCUGUUUACAAUAUGCUUUAAUGAGUUAAAUCUGGGGGAUGUGGAUAGAAUUUUAGUAUCCUAGCUUUGGCAUUCUUCCAUGACUUUGGGCCAAUUAUUUAAUAAUUCCAAGCCUGCAUCUUUGUUAGAAUCUCUAAAUUUCUCUACUCCUGUUAUUAUCCUCAGAACAGGACUGUGAGGUGCAGUAGGCCACAUGGUGUAGUGGUUUAGGUGGACAGACUUGCCAGUGCUGUUCUCAUGGAUAGCCUAGGACUGUCCCUAGCUCUCUGCAGUGACAGUGAUAGUGACUGGUGAAGGUGAAGGGAUCCACCCAGACGUUCUUCCUGAUGGAGAGAGGCUGGCCUGUGGCUCUUCCCUGGGGUGGAUGUUAACCUGCUAACGUGACAUAUCUAGUCCUGCUUACAUUACUAAGUGGUAGGAAAUUUUAGGUAACACCUCAGACUUUAAAGUGGCCUACUGAGCUGGUAGAAAAGUGUGUAGUUGGUGCUCAGUAAUUGUUGAAAAGAUAGAAGCUUUACUUCAAAGCUCUUGUAGUUUGAUCAGUUUGGAAAAAAUAUUUUAAUGUUGGGCUCUGUUAACAGCUGGACUGGUGGCUGUCUGAAUUGGGACCAUGCUUGGGGUGAGGUUUUUUCUUACUUUUUUUUUUUUUUUUGGUGAGACAGAGUCUUGCUCUGUCGCCCAGGCUGGAGUACAGUGGUGCAAUCUCGGCCCACUGCAGCCUCUGCCUCCUGGGUUCAAGCGAUUCUCCUGCCUCAGUUUUCUGAGUAGCUGGGACUACAAGCAUGUGCCACCACGCCUGGCUAAUUUUUUUCUAUUUUUAGCAGAGAUGGGGUUUCACCAUUUUAGUCAGGAUGGUCUUGAUCUCCUGAACUUGUGAUCCAUCCACCUCAGCCUCCCAAAGUGCUGGGAUUACAGGCGUGAGCCACCGCAUCUGGCCACAUAUUUUUUUAAAUUAAAUGUGAUACAUAAAAUUAGGCUGCAGGCAUGGCCUGAUUUGCAGGUGCUUCAUGAGCAAGCGUGCACAGCAUUUAUUUGCUGCUCCUGGAGUCUCUCGUGUGUGCUUGUAGCCUAGCCUUAAGCCCUCUGUGGACGGCUUGGAAUGCGUACUCCAAAUGACUCUUUUGGCGGGGUGGGAAGUGGCAAUACUUUAGGUGACUGACAGUUGAAAUUAACCUUACACAAGAGCCAAACUGUAGGCUGAUGCAGGGCCACUCACCUUUGUACUCACCCCUGGCAGGUCCUGUAAGAGGUGCUACUUGCUUCCACUUUGCCAGCUGUUCGUUGGCCCUGUUUUGUCUUCUGCUGUUUGCCUUAUUUAUGAAACAGAAUGGAAACAGGCGAGUUUGAUUUGUUAUAAUUCCUAGGAGUCAUAGAAUGGAAGCAGGUGAGUUUGAUUUGUUAUAAUUCCUAGGAUUGGAUAAUUUGCCUUCCCCUCUCUCCAUCUUUAAUUAAUCCCUUAAAGGAAAAGAGGACGACAGCACUUUUCCUGCAGUCAUCUGUGUAGGCCUCAGCCUUAACUCAUGACAUAGGCUGGUGCCACUGGCCACAGGGCUGACCUCAGCUCUUGGAGCCCAUGGGGUGACAGGAGAUCAGCACCUUUGAGGUGGCGGCGUGAGGCGUCUUCCAGGCCUUGCUCAUGGUGCUUGAAAACACUGCUUUAGAGCUUUGUUAAGAGAGAGAGGCCCUACUUACUCCUGUCCCACAGGCAUUUGGGUGUUGACCUCCUUGUUGGCCUCUUAAGGAGAGAAUACUUGAGUAUUGAAUUCGAUCAGCUUUUCUGCCUCCAGGGACCCUGUUUCUCUCUGCUGAGACUGUGGCGGAUGAAACCAGGAUUUAGUGGAUGGUCACCAGGUAGCUUGGGCAGACCUGGGCCGCGGGGCCCCUGAGGACUCAUACGUCUUUUUCCUGUUCACAUGUUCCUUCCCCACACCUUGGCCCAUUCUCAGUCCCUCCCAUGCUCCUUAGCGUGAGGCACUCAGGGAGGUGCCCAUGGGGCCUUGGGGCCUGUGCUGGAGCUGGUUCCCAGCCUCAGAAGUGUGCCUAACUGUGCCACAUUCAUUGGAAAGCUGCUUUCACACUUCCUGGAUGGAAUUCUCUCAUUUUUUCAAUAUAAAGUCACUGAGAUGAUUUUUUUGGAGAAGUCUUUAAAGGCCAGUUAUACAUUUAUUGAUACUUGGUAUUGACAAAGUUCAGUUGUUUAGUGUUGCUAAGUCAUACUGUGUAAGUUUGUUGAGCACAGAGUUUUCAUUUUAUACUUUCAGAGGAGAAAUGAAACUGAAUUUCGUGGCCAGAAAUAUGUUUGAGCGUCAUCCUGAUAAGCAGCUAUGAGAAGAGAGGUGGUGAAACGGAUCGAAACUGUGGUGAAAGACCUUUGGCCGACGGCUGAUGUACAGAUAUUUGGCAGCUUUAGUACAGGUCUUUAUCUUCCAACUAGCGACAUAGACCUGGUGGUCUUCGGGAAAUGGGAGCGUCCUCCUUUACAGCUGCUGGAGCAAGCCCUGCGGAAGCACAACGUGGCUGAGCCGUGUUCCAUCAAAGUCCUUGACAAGGCUACGGUACCAAUAAUAAAGCUCACAGAUCAGGAGACUGAAGUGAAAGUUGACAUCAGCUUUAACAUGGAGACGGGCGUCCGGGCAGCGGAGUUCAUCAAGAAUUACAUGAAGAAAUAUUCAUUGCUGCCUUACUUGAUUUUAGUAUUGAAACAGUUCCUUCUGCAGAGGGACCUGAAUGAAGUUUUUACAGGUGGAAUUAGCUCAUACAGCCUAAUUUUAAUGGCCAUUAGCUUUCUACAGUUGCAUCCAAGAAUUGAUGCCCGGAGAGCUGAUGAAAACCUUGGAAUGCUUCUUGUAGAAUUUUUUGAACUCUAUGGGAGAAAUUUUAAUUACUUGAAAACCGGUAUUAGAAUCAAAGAAGGAGGUGCCUAUAUCGCCAAAGAGGAGAUCAUGAAAGCCAUGACCAGCGGGUACAGACCGUCGAUGCUGUGCAUUGAGGACCCCCUGCUGCCAGGGAAUGACGUUGGCCGGAGCUCCUAUGGCGCCAUGCAGGUGAAGCAGGUCUUCGAUUAUGCCUACAUAGUGCUCAGCCAUGCUGUGUCACCGCUGGCCAGGUCCUAUCCAAACAGAGACGCCGAAAGUACUUUAGGAAGAAUCAUCAAAGUAACUCAGGAGGUGAUUGACUACCGGAGGUGGAUCAAAGAGAAGUGGGGCAGCAAAGCCCACCCGUCGCCAGGCAUGGACAGCAGGAUCAAGAUCAAAGAGCGAAUAGCCACAUGCAAUGGGGAGCAGACGCAGAACCGAGAGCCCGAGUCUCCCUAUGGCCAGCGCUUGACUUUGUCGCUGUCCAGCCCCCAGCUCCUGUCUUCAGGCUCCUCGGCCUCUUCUGUGUCUUCACUUUCUGGGAGUGACGUUGAUUCAGACACACCGCCCUGCACAACGCCCAGUGUUUACCAGUUCAGUCUGCAAGCGCCAGCUCCUCUCAUGGCCGGCUUACCCACCGCCUUGCCAAUGCCCAGUGGCAAACCUCAGCCCACCACUUCCAGAACACUGAUCAUGACAACCAACAAUCAGACCAGGUUUACUAUACCUCCACCGACCCUAGGGGUUGCUCCUGUUCCUUGCAGACAAGCUGGUGUAGAAGGAACUGCGUCUUUGAAAGCCGUCCACCACAUGUCUUCCCCGGCCAUUCCCUCAGCGUCCCCCAACCCGCUCUCGAGCCCUCAUCUGUAUCAUAAGCAGCACAACGGCAUGAAACUGUCCAUGAAGGGCUCUCACGGCCACACCCAAGGCGGCGGCUACAGCUCUGUGGGUAGCGGAGGUGUGCGGCCCCCUGUGGGCAACAGGGGACACCACCAGUAUAACCGCACCGGCUGGAGGAGGAAAAAACACACACACACACGGGACAGUCUGCCCGUGAGCCUCAGCAGAUAAUGGCUCCUGGCUGCGUCAGCCUCCCCCACCCCUCUGCAGACUGCCCCGCGGCCUCGGCCACCGGCAGGGGAACCGAGACCAGCACCCCGCACGUCAGCCGGGCUCGCGGCACGCCCGCCGCUGAUCACUCUGCAUGUUUCUUCGUGUGGUGGUCGCGUCCAUCUUCAAGAACAGCUCGUUGUGCUCAUCUGUGAAGCCUUAUUAAACGUGGACGUUGUUUUCUGCCUUCCCAGGAUUCUUCCUUCAGUGCUGAGGCAGGUCGGGCUCAGGAACUGCAGGGACGUGAACAUGCGCUUGCGGUUUGAGGUAGCCGUGUCUGUUCCUUCGCGGUUUGCUAUUUUCAUUUCCUGUUCGUCAAAGCAGCAGAGGAGAUCAAACCCCGUUCGUGUGUCUUUCCUCCACGGAUAAGCUUGGGAGGUCAUUGUUUUACUGCCCUCACAUUUUGUUUGAAAUUUCAGAACUGUUUUUCUAUGUAAAUAUUGAAAACUUAUGAUUUGUGCAAUAACUCAGAUAUUUUUUAUUUAAUUUCCUAUUUUCACAUAAGUUAUAUUUAAGGGAGGAGGGAAUUUUUUUUAAACAAGCUUAGGUCCUUUCCCGAGCUGCAUUUUCUAAGUUGGGUCAUCGUGUCGGCUGGUUGUCUGACGAGCAUCGUUACAAACACCAUGAUGAGGGGUUUGGGGUUUUAUUUUGAUGUCUUUUCUUUUGGUCGGAAGUGAGUGAAGGAGCCAGGUCGCCCUGAAGGUUUUCCAAAGGGCUUGGCUCCAGAGCCACCUGGCAGACUGCCCGUGGCCCUGCUGUCGGGCCCCAGGCCGUUGUCCUGCUCUGACCACAGAGUUUUAAUGUUUUGGUUUUCACUUCUUUUAAACUGGACAACAAAUCCAGCAUUUCAAGUGCCAGAAGUAUAACUUUCUAAGGAGAGAAGGGUUGUCACAUUAUAAAAUCUUUAGGAAAAUGUGAACUGGAAAACGCUUCGGUCAGUUUUAGUGACAUAGCCUGUGAUGAUGGGUCUGGUGACUAUUAUUGCGGACCGUGGUACCCAGUUUUAGGAAUGUGGAGAAAGGAAUUCUGUUGAUUCCGUUGAGGAAUCUGUAGCGUAUGCAUUCGUUCUGUUAAGAGCAAAUCUAGGAGAAGUGCUUCAGCUGCCCAGUGCGCCGUGGGGAGUGUUUUAACGGAUCGUGUCGCAGGAGAGCACAGCCCAGCGUUGGGGCCGGGACCGCUGGCGCCCGACGUCGGAAGCAUACAGGUAUACUAUGCAAGUGUAUUCUGCCACAACAACCACUGUCUUUGUUACCUUUUUUUGAACAAGAAUAUAUCCAUCCUGCCUAACCCUGAGUUUUUGGAGCACCACAGUUGUCCUGGGAGUUGGUUGCAUCUUGUAGGCCAUCUGACUUCCUGUUUUUAAAACGGGGGUCUGGUCUUGCUAAACACUACAGGUAGGUUGGUCUUUGAAGUCCACUAGUGGAGAAUGUCAAGACAAGAUACUUAUUACCAUGACAUCUGAUGCAUGUGCAGCAGUGGGGAGUUCUAGAUUGAUCUCUGAAUGUGAUCGACGCCCAGCAAGGACAAGCUUUAAAAUGUCUGCGGUCUGCCCUUUUGAAGCAGGACUGGCUCACUCUGUCAUUGGGAGCUGUCAGCUGCGACUGCAGGUUCUCUAGGAGGCAUUCCAGAAUAGAGUAGCACACUGUGUCUGCAGUUCUCGAUGACCGAAAGUUAUCAAAAAUAUUUAAAAUAUUUAAAUUGUGAACCUAUUGAUAAAGAAUAUUUAUAAAAACUGAUCUGUAGGCCUGUACUAAUCUCUACGCAUUAGCAAUAUUGACUGUAAACCCACAUUAAGGAAACCACUACGGGUCUGGCAGUGCGUGUCCCGUGGGGUGUGCAUUUUAAAACUCGAUUCAUAGACACAGGUACCAUGUUCCAUUUCCGUCAUGGUGAAGCAAAUGAAUUGGCCUGGCUACCACUGUGGUCGCGUGCUACAGGUUUGACAAAAAGAUAUCAUGUUUCGAUUUUUUUGUGUGUGGACAACAAUAUGGAAGCUAAAAUUGACAUAUUUUUAUGUAAAGUUUUUCUAUUCUUUGAUUUUUAAUAAACUUUGGAAACCA